AGCCUCCUUAGUCUCCUCAUCCUGCUUCACAGGCUCCGCGGCCUCCGGCCUCCUCGGCCCCCGUCCCCCGGCCUCCUCGGCCCCCGUCCCCCGCCAUCCGCCGCCCGGAUCCUCGCCGCCCUCCCUAGGCCGCCCCGCCGCCAUGGGCCUGCGCCCGCCGCGCCGCCGGGCCGAGGGCAGCUGAGGCGCGGUGCGAAGAUGGGCGAGGACAGAGCAGGGCCCGAGCGCCAGCCCCAGCAGCCCGGGCGCCCCGCGCGCGCCCGCCCGCGCCGCCGAGGGGAUGCCCGCGCCCGCCGCCGCGCCCUGAGCGCCUUUGUCUGCCGCCCGCGCCCUUCCGCACCACUAGCCUCUCGGGAGCAUGGCGUCGGCCCCGCCGGCCUCGCCCCCGGGCUCGGAGCCGCCGGGGCCCGACCCGGAGCCGGGCGGGCCGGACGGGCCGGGGGCGGCACAACUGGCUCCGGGCCCUGCGGAGCUACGCCUCGGAGCGCCCGUCGGCGGCCCCGACCCGCAGUCCCCGGGCCUGGAUGAGCCUGCGCCCGGGGCCGCUGCAGAUGGCGGGGCGCGUUGGAGCGCCGGGCCGGCCCCGGGGCUGGAGGGAGGCCCGCGAGACCCCGGGCCGUCCGCCCCGCCGCCGCGCUCCGGCCCGCGGGGGCAGCUUGCGAGCCCCGACGCCCCGGGCCCAGGGCCGCGCUCCGAAGCGCCGCUUCCAGAACUCGACCCGUUGUUCUCCUGGACUGAGGAGCCCGAGGAGUGUGGCCCCGCGAGCUGCCCGGAGAGCGCGCCUUUCCGCUUGCAGGGGUCCAGCAGCAGCCACCGAGCGCGGGGCGAGGUCGACGUCUUCUCUCCCUUCCCCGCGCCCACGGCGGGCGAGCUGGCGCUGGAGCAAGGUCCCGGGUCCCCGCCGCAGCCCUCGGACCUCAGCCAGACCCACCCCCUUCCGAGCGAGCCCGUGGGGAGUCAGGAGGACGGCCCCCGCCUCCGAGCCGUGUUCGAUGCCCUGGACGGGGAUGGGGACGGUUUCGUCCGCAUCGAGGACUUCAUCCAGUUUGCUACGGUCUACGGGGCAGAGCAGGUGAAGGACUUAACUAAGUACUUGGAUCCCAGUGGGCUCGGCGUGAUCAGCUUUGAAGACUUCUACCAAGGGAUCACAGCCAUCAGAAACGGAGAUCCUGAUGGCCAGUGCUACGGUGGUGUCGCUUCUGCCCAAGAUGAGGAGCCCCUGGCCUGCCCGGACGAGUUCGAUGACUUCGUCACCUAUGAGGCCAACGAGGUGACGGACAGCGCGUACAUGGGCUCCGAGAGCACCUACAGUGAGUGUGAGACCUUCACGGACGAGGACACCAGCACCCUGGUGCACCCUGAGCUGCAACCUGAAGGGGACGCAGACAGUGCCGGCGGCUCGGCCGUGCCCUCUGAGUGCCUGGACGCCAUGGAGGAGCCCGACCAUGGUGCCCUGCUGCUGCUCCCAGGCAGGCCUCACCCCCAUGGCCAGUCUGUCAUCACGGUGAUCGGGGGCGAGGAGCACUUUGAGGACUACGGUGAAGGCAGUGAGGCGGAGCUGUCCCCAGAGACCCUAUGCAACGGGCAGCUGGGCUGCAGUGACCCCGCUUUCCUCACGCCCAGCACUGACCCUCUUGCCGCAAAGCUGCACAGCAUCCUCACUGAUGAGGCGUUUGAGUUUUACUGUAGCCAGUGCCACAAACAAAUCAACCGCCUUGAGGAUCUUUCUGCCCGCCUGAGUGAUCUUGAAAUGAAUAGUCCGACAAAGCGGCUCUCCAGCAAGAAGGUGGCAAGGUACCUGCACCAGUCAGGGGCCCUGACCAUGGAGGCCCUGGAGGACCCUUCCCCCGAGCUCAUGGAGGGCCCAGAGGAGGACAUUGCUGACAAGGUUGUCUUCCUGGAAAGGCGUGUGCUGGAGCUGGAAAAGGACACGGCAGCCACCGGUGAGCAACACAGCCGCCUGAGGCAGGAGAACCUGCAGCUGGUGCACAGAGCAAACGCCCUGGAGGAGCAGCUGAAGGAGCAGGAGCUGAGAGCCUGCGAGAUGGUCCUGGAAGAGACCCGGCGUCAGAAGGAGCUCCUGUGCAAGAUGGAGAGGGAGAAGAGCAUUGAGAUCGAGAACCUGCAGACCAGGCUACAGCAACUGGACGAGGAGAACAGUGAACUCCGGUCCUGCACGCCCUGUCUGAAGGCCAACAUUGAGCGUCUGGAGGAGGAGAAGCAGAAGCUGUUGGAUGAGAUAGAGUCGCUGACGCUGCGGCUCAGUGAAGAGCAGGAGAACAAGAGGAGAAUGGGGGACAGGCUGAGUCACGAGAGGCACCAGUUCCAGAGGGACAAGGAGGCCACCCAGGAGCUGAUCGAGGACCUCCGAAAGCAGCUGGAGCACCUGCAGCUCCUCAAGCUGGAGGCCGAGCAGCGGCGGGGCCGCAGCAGCAGCAUGGGCCUGCAGGAGUACCACAGCCGCGCCCGGGAGAGCGAGCUGGAGCAGGAGGUCCGCAGGCUGAAGCAGGACAACCGCAACCUGAAGGAGCAGAACGAGGAGCUGAACGGGCAGAUCAUUACCCUCAGCAUCCAGGGCGCCAAGAGCCUCUUCUCCACAGCCUUCUCUGAGUCCCUGGCUGCAGAGAUCAGCUCCGUCUCCCGAGAUGAGCUCAUGGAGGCGAUUCAGAAGCAGGAGGAGAUCAACUUCCGCCUGCAGGACUACAUCGACAGGAUCAUCGUGGCCAUCAUGGAGACCAACCCGUCCAUCCUGGAGGUCAAGUAGAGGCAGGAAGGUCCAGCCUGAGCUGGAUUCGGGACUCCAACACCCUGGAGUGGUUCCGUCAGACCAUGAGGAGCCAAGACCAGCAGGUCCCACAGCCGACAGUGCCCAGAGCAUGCAGGGAACCCUCGUGCAGCUGAGCUGGGGCCGCCAAAGACCGGGGCUGCCAAAGGGGCAGAGGGUGGUGGAGAGGAGAGGGAGAAAGGGAAGUCCCAGGGCCCGGGGUCCACAGAGGAUGAGGGUUGUGGCAGGGCCGUCCAUCAGCGCUGACCUUCCGGGGGCCCAGAGCUUCCCAGCCCUGAGUCAAGCUGGCCAUGAACGCGUACACUUCAGUUCAGCAGGAUGGGCUGGAGAGCCUCUCUGUGCAGCGGUGUGGGGUGAGCCCUGCUGUGGCCUCCUUGUGGUGGUCCCUCUUCCCACGUGCAGCCCUGUUGGGAAGAAAGGAAGAAAACAGGUCCCUCCAGGGGUGCUGCUGCCUAAGCCACCCACAUAAGUACGCUGGUGCCGUGUCACCCAUGUUGAGCCGCUCCUGAUGGCUGACGGGCUCCCAGACCCUCACCUCGGACAUGGUGGUGGGGGAAGGACGGGUGGGCAAGGCUGGUGCGUUCCCCAGCUCUCCCUACGCUGCUCGGGCCAUUGCCCAGCCAGAUGUGGUCACCUCAGUCCAGCUCUGGGGCCUCCAGGCCAUGUGGCUGUUCCCACGGCCCAGUCCUCGCUGCAGUAACCCCUGGGGGCUCUGACCACCUAUGGGGGCCGGGCAGGAGCCUCUGGGGCCUCCACUCCGACAUCAGGACCUGAGAUGACCGCUGUGUGGCGCUCUCUCCCUGGGCAGGGUGGAUGCCACAGGCCCCUCUGGCUCCCAGGUGCUGCUUCUCCACAGGUGCGGCCUGGCCCGGCCUCCUAAAGGCCACACCCUCCCCACGCACUUCCCAGGCCAGAAUCCAAACAUCGGGAACCCUGUUUUCUUCUGGGUGUGUCUCACUUAGAAAUCGUGGUUCUUCCCCGAGGGUGCAUGUUGCAGGAGGGAGAGGGCAGGGAAGACUCACAGCAGAGCAGGAGGGGGCCUGUGCUUCUCGGGGUCUGCACCCCAGGCACAGCGGUGUCACCCCGCAGGACCGCGGGCCUGCCCCAACCCCCAGCAUUCCCGGGUGGGCCCAGACCCCAUCACCAAGACUGGCCACCCGCUGCGUGUGUGUGCGCGCGCGUGUACGUGUGGCCCCACAUCCGCCGCCUUCCACGCUAGGAUGUAAGAGGUCGCCUCCUAUUGUACAUUUGGGGAAAGCCUUGGGUGUAAAUCAGUGUAAACUUGGAGGAGAGAUUUUUCUAUCAUGUAGAGUAGGUAUUUUUUAUAGAUUGAAGGUUGAUCAAUUUUUUAAUACUUUCAAGAGAAAACUGUGUAUACACAUGAAAUAUAUAUAUAUAUAUAUAUAUAUAUAUGUAUAAUAUAUAAAGACUGGCACCCUGCCUCUCUGUGCCCAGGCCCAGCCCUGGUGACAUGGCACCACUCAGCAGUGCUGUCACUGUAAGCAUGGACUCCCAGGAGACAGUGUGGGAAACGCUCCUGCUUUAAUUCCCCGAGAAACGGCUCUUCCUGCCUGGAUGCAGGAGGGCAGGGGCCACCACAGAUUAAAGCUGUUACUGCACACGCAGAGGCCGGCUUCUUCCUCCAGGGGGGCCACAGGGUGGGGUGGGAGUCUUCUGGGCCUGGCCCAGCUUCCCUCAAGGCGUCCGAGGCCAUCAGUUGUCUGAGCUCAGAACCCAGCAGACCUGCCUGGCUCUGCAGCUUGGUCAGACUAAGACCCUUCCAAGGCCGUAGGAUUGCACCUCCAGGCCCAGUGGAGCCUGGCAGCUUUCCAGCCAGGUUCUGGAUCCUGACGAGCUGCUGAGACAGCAUCAAGGUGGGGCAGGUGGGGCGGGGCAAAUUGGGCAGCACAGGGCUGUGUGGGCAUCAGGGCUCUGGGUCACACGCCUCUGGGGACGUACGUCCCAUGUCGGGAGAGCCGUCAAAACGUCCCCGGGAUUAAGAGAAGAGUGGGGGGCAGGGCGCAGAGGCUCACGCCAUAAUCUCAGCACUUUGGGAGGCCAAGGCAGGAGGAUCGCUUGAACCCGGGAGUUCAAGACCAGCCUGGGCAACAUAGCAAGGCCCCAUCUCUAAAAAAUAAAAAAUUAACCAGG